GAAACAGUGACUGGAAAAGAAUUAUCACAUUGCACAAGGAUGGCUCUGAAAUGGACUACAGUUCUGCUGAUACAACUCAGUUUUUACUUUAGCUCUGGGAGUUGUGGAAAGGUGCUGGUAUGGGCCGCAGAAUACAGCCUUUGGAUGAAUAUGAAGACAAUCCUGAAAGAACUUGUUCAGAGAGGUCAUGAGGUGACUGUACUGGCAUCUUCAGCUUCCAUUCUUUUUGAUCCCAACGACUCAUCCACUCUUAAACUUGAAGUUUAUCCUACAUCUUUAACUAAAACUGAAUUUGAGAAUAUCAUCAUGCAAUUGGUUAAGAGAUUGUCAGAAAUUCAAAAAGAUACAUUUUGGUUACCUUUUUCACAAGAACAAGAAAUCCUGUGGGCAAUUAAUGACAUAAUUAGAAACUUCUGUAAAGAUGUAGUUUCAAAUAAGAAACUUAUGAAAAAACUACAAGAGUCAAGAUUUGACAUCGUUUUUGCAGAUGCUUAUUUACCCUGUGGUGAGCUGCUGGCUGAGCUAUUUAACAUACCCUUUGUGUACAGUCACAGCUUCAGUCCUGGCUACUCAUUUGAAAGGCACAGUGGAGGAUUUAUUUUCCCUCCUUCCUACGUACCUGUUGUUAUGUCAAAAUUAAGUGAUCAAAUGACUUUCAUGGAGAGGGUAAAAAAUAUGCUCUAUGUGCUUUAUUUUGACUUUUGGUUCCAAAUAUUUAAUAUGAAGAAGUGGGAUCAGUUUUACAGUGAAGUUUUAGGAAGACCCACUACAUUAUCUGAGACAAUGAGGAAAGCUGACAUAUGGCUUAUGCGAAACUCCUGGAAUUUUAAAUUUCCUCAUCCAUUCUUACCAAAUGUUGAUUUUGUUGGAGGACUCCACUGCAAACCUGCCAAACCCCUACCUAAGGAGUUUGUACAGAGCUCUGGAGAAAAUGGUGUUGUGGUGUUUUCUCUGGGGUCAAUGGUCAGUAACAUGACAGAAGAAAGGGCCAACGUAAUUGCAACAGCCCUUGCCAAGAUCCCACAAAAGGUUCUUUGGAGAUUUGAUGGGAAUAAACCAGAUGCCUUAGGUCUCAAUACUCGACUGUACAAGUGGAUACCCCAGAAUGACCUUCUAGGUCAUCCAAAAACCAGAGCUUUUAUAACUCAUGGUGGAGCCAAUGGCAUCUAUGAGGCAAUCUACCAUGGGAUCCCUAUGGUGGGCAUUCCAUUGUUUUUUGAUCAACCUGAUAAUAUUGCUCACAUGAAGGCCAAGGGAGCAGCUGUUAGAGUGGACUUCAACACAAUGUCGAGUACAGACCUGCUGAAUGCACUGAAGACAGUAAUUAAUGAUCCUUCAUAUAAAGAGAAUAUUAUGAAAUUAUCAAGAAUUCAACAUGAUCAACCAGUGAAGCCCCUGGAUCGAGCAGUCUUCUGGAUUGAAUUUGUCAUGCGCCACAAAGGAGCCAAACAUCUUCGAGUUGCAGCCCACAACCUCACCUGGUUCCAGUACCACUCUUUGGAUGUGAUUGGGUUCCUGCUGGCUUGUGUGGCAACCGUGCUAUUUAUCAUCACAAAGUGUUGUCUGUUUUGUUUCUGGAAGUUUGCUAGAAAAGGAAAGAAGGGAAAAAGGGAUUAGUUAUAUCUGAGAUUUGAAGCUGGAAAACCUGAUAGAUAGGAAUACUUCAGUUGAUUCCAGCAAUAAAUAUUGUGAUGCAAGAUUUCUUUCUUCCUGUGACAAAAAAAAAUCCUUUCGAAGUCUACCUUGUCAAGUAAAAAUUUGUUUUUCAGAGAUUUACCACCCAGUUAAUGGUUAGAAAUAUUCUGUGGCAAUGAAGAAAACACUAGGGGAAAUAAAAAAUAAUAUAAAGCCAUAUGAGCUUGUAUUGAAAUUUGUUGCACUUAUAUUGAAAUGUGAUCAUGGCUCACUUCAGCCUCAACUUACUAAGCUCAAGAGGUUCUCUCACCUCAGCCCCCCAAGUAGCUGGGACCAUAGGUGCAUGUCACCAUGUCCAACUAAUUUUUUAUUUUUUGUAGUGAUGAGAUCUCAUUGUGUUCUCCAUGCUGAUUUCAAACUCCUGGGCUCAAACAAUCCUCCCAUUUUAGCAUCCCAAAGGGAUGAGAUUACAGGUAUGUACCACCAUAACUUUACAAAAUGAGAUUUUUAUAUAAGAAUGAUUCAAAUGUUCAGGGAUGAAAGAGUCACUAACAUAAAAGAAGAAUGGGAUGAGGUGAGAAGGAUGAAUACAAAAAUAAUUAGAUAUUCUUGAAAUCAGAAAUGUGCUCCCUAAUUAUAUGAAAUGUUGUUUGAUUACAUAAAAUAAAGUGGAAAUGAAUGAUUGACUGAACAGCCCACAAGAAGAAUCACUUAAUGCUCUGAAAAUUACCAGUAAACUGAUUAAAAUCUAAAAUUGCUUUCUGUUAAAGCUUUACUGAUUAGUUUUUCUUCCAAAGCUCUCUUGUUUCUAGUUGUUUUCUUGGUCUUAACUACCCAUUAUAUGCUUUGUUAAAGUGUUUAUGCCCUGAUUCAAUGUGAUUAUCUCAAUUUUUAUUUCAUUCUGUCCUAACUCUUGCAACCUGCAUGUCCUCUUUAUUAUUGAUCAAUCCAACUGCAAAGUUCACCUUACCUGACUAAGGAUUAUUCAUUAAGUUUUACUUGUUUAUCUGACAUUUAUUAUUUUGUCUCUUUGCUAGUCACUCUGAGCCAUGGUCAUGAUGACUUAGGAUUCUGGAUCUCUUAUGAAUAACAAAUUUAUCCUUAAUAAAGUCUCUAUACUAAAGAA